AGGGAGGAGGAAGCGGUGGCUGCUGCGGAUGUCGGUGUGAGCGAGCGGCGCCUGAACACACGGCGGCUGCCGAGCGCCUGACCCGGGCCUGCGCCAGAGCCUGCACCGAGCUCCGGGGCCCCACACCCGCUACGGUGGCCCUGCGCCCGUUGCUACUGAGGCGGCGUGCUCUGCAUUCUUCGCUGUCCAGGCCUGCCGGCUCUGGUGUCUGCUGGCUCCUCCUUGCUCGCCUGCUCCCUCCUGCUUGCCUGAGUCACCGCCGCCGCCGCCGCCACAGCCAUGGCCGAGAGUGGUGAAAGCGGCGGUCCUCCGGGCUCCCAGGAUAGCGCCGCCGGAGCCGAAGGUGCUGGCGCCCCCGCGGCCGCUGCCUCCGCGGAGCCCAAAAUCAUGAAAGUCACCGUGAAGACCCCGAAGGAAAAGGAGGAAUUCGCCGUGCCCGAGAAUAGCUCCGUCCAGCAGUUUAAGGAAGAAAUCUCUAAACGUUUUAAAUCACAUACUGACCAACUUGUGUUGAUAUUUGCUGGAAAAAUUUUGAAAGAUCAAGAUACCUUGAGUCAGCAUGGAAUUCAUGAUGGACUUACUGUUCACCUUGUCAUUAAAACACAAAACAGGCCUCAGGAUCAUUCAGCUCAGCAAACAAAUACAGCUGGAAGCAAUGUUACUACAUCAUCAACUCCUAAUAGUAACUCUACAUCUGGUUCUGCUACUAGCAACCCUUUUGGUUUAGGUGGCCUUGGGGGACUUGCAGGUCUGAGUAGCUUGGGUUUGAAUACUACCAACUUCUCUGAACUACAGAGUCAGAUGCAGCGACAACUUUUGUCUAACCCUGAAAUGAUGGUCCAGAUCAUGGAAAAUCCCUUUGUUCAGAGCAUGCUCUCAAAUCCUGACCUGAUGAGACAGUUAAUUAUGGCCAAUCCACAAAUGCAGCAGUUGAUACAGAGAAAUCCAGAAAUUAGUCAUAUGUUGAAUAAUCCAGAUAUAAUGAGACAAACGUUGGAACUUGCCAGGAAUCCAGCAAUGAUGCAGGAGAUGAUGAGGAACCAGGACCGAGCUUUGAGCAACCUAGAAAGCAUCCCAGGGGGAUAUAAUGCUUUAAGGCGCAUGUACACAGAUAUUCAGGAACCAAUGCUGAGUGCUGCACAAGAGCAGUUUGGUGGUAAUCCAUUUGCUUCCUUGGUGAGCAAUACAUCCUCUGGUGAAGGUAGUCAACCUUCCCGUACAGAAAAUAGAGAUCCACUACCCAAUCCAUGGGCUCCACAGACUUCCCAGAGUUCAUCAGCUUCCAGCGGCACUGCCAGCACUGUGGGUGGCACUACUGGUAGUACUGCCAGUGGCACUUCUGGGCAGAGUACUACUGCGCCAAAUUUGGUGCCUGGAGUAGGAGCUAGUAUGUUCAACACACCAGGAAUGCAGAGCUUGUUGCAACAAAUAACUGAAAACCCACAACUGAUGCAAAACAUGUUGUCUGCCCCCUACAUGAGAAGCAUGAUGCAGUCACUAAGCCAGAAUCCUGACCUUGCUGCACAGAUGAUGCUGAAUAAUCCCCUAUUUGCUGGAAAUCCUCAGCUUCAAGAACAAAUGAGACAACAGCUCCCAACUUUCCUCCAACAAAUGCAGAAUCCUGAUACACUAUCAGCAAUGUCAAACCCUAGAGCAAUGCAGGCCUUGUUACAGAUUCAGCAGGGUUUACAGACAUUAGCAACGGAAGCCCCGGGCCUCAUCCCAGGGUUUACUCCUGGCUUGGGGGCAUUAGGAAGCACUGGAGGCUCUUCGGGAACUAAUGGAUCUAACGCCACACCUAGUGAAAACACAAGUCCCACAGCAGGAACCACUGAACCUGGACAUCAGCAGUUUAUUCAGCAGAUGCUGCAGGCUCUUGCUGGAGUAAAUCCUCAGCUACAGAAUCCAGAAGUCAGAUUUCAGCAACAACUGGAACAACUCAGUGCAAUGGGAUUUUUGAACCGUGAAGCAAACUUGCAAGCUCUAAUAGCAACAGGAGGUGAUAUCAAUGCAGCUAUUGAAAGGUUACUGGGCUCCCAGCCAUCAUAGCAGCAUUUCUGUAUCUUGAAAAAAUGUAAUUUAUUUUUGAUAACGGCUCUUAAACUUUAAAAUACCUGCUUUAUUUCAUUUUGACUCUUGGAAUUCUGUGCUGUUAUAAACAAACCCAAUAUGAUGCAUUUUAAGGUGGAGUACAGUAAGAUGUGUGGGUUUUUCUGUAUUUUUCUUUUCUGGAACAGUGGGAAUUAAGGCUACUGCAUGCAUCACUUCUGCAUUUAUUGUAAUUUUUUAAAAACAUCACCUUUUAUAGUUGGGUGACCAGAUUUUGUCCUGCAUCUGUCCAGUUUAUUUGCUUUUUAAACAUUAGCCUAUGGUAGUAAUUUAUGUAGAAUAAAAGCAUUAAAAAGAAGCAAAUCAUUUGCACUCUAUAAUUUGUGGUACAGUAUUGCUUAUUGUGACUUUGGCAUGCAUUUUUGCAAACAAUGCUGUAAGAUUUAUACUACUGAUAAUUUUGUUUUAUUUGUAUACAAUAUAGAGUAUGCACAUUUGGGACUGCAUUUCUGGAAACAUACUGCAAUAGGCUCUCUGAGCAAAACACCUGUAACUAAAAAAGUGAAGAUAAGAAAAUACUCUUAAAGCUGAGUAUUUCCUAAUUGUAUAGAAUCUUACAGCAUCUUUGACAAACAUCUCCCAGCAAAAGUGCCGGUUAGUCAGGUUUGUUGAAAAUACAGUAGAAAAGCUGAUUCUGGUUAUCUCUUUAAGGACAAUUAAUUGUACAGACACAUAAUGUAACAUUGUCUCAACAUUCAUUCACAGAUUGACUGUAAAUUACCUUAAUCUUUGUGCAGACUGAAGGAACACUGUAGUAUACCCCAAAGUGCAUUUGCCUAGGACUUCUCAGCUUCUCCCAUAGGUAGUUUAACAGGCAUUAAAAUUUGUAAUUGAAAUGUUGCUUUCACUGAAAAAGUGUCUUGAUGUUUCAGUUAUUUUUAAUCGCCAUAAAAAAAUAGAACUAUCUUUUGGGUUUAUCUGUUUUCUCAUGCACAGGCAAUACACAAAUUUAAAAUGAGUUGUGAGCCAAUUGUUUCUGAAGUGUUUUGGUAGUUCUAUUAAGAAAUAGUUAAAUAUUGUGCUUUUCAGAGCCUCAGAGAAAGGGGGACGGGGUGGGGGGGUGGGGCAGCGGAAUCUGUCCUGGAUGGGGCCAGCUUAAAUAAUACUGGCAACCAAGAUUCUGUUAGGAUUUCUGUGCAUAUAGUGUAGUAAAGAAGUAUCAUUCAGGGGUGAAAAACAAAGAGCCGUUUUAAUGAUGUUGAGUACAUUUGGCUGUUUUAUAGCCUUUUUCUUCCCUCCCCCAAAGAAUUCUGUUUGCCUAACUCCCAAACUGUUGGGGUGGUACAUUCCUUUAGGACCAAUUAAAACAUAAUUGAGGGUCAGUGAUACAUUUGGCUGACUCUGGUUCAGUAUUCUCUUAGGUGAUUAUAUUCUCUCAUGUACAGUUACAGGAAAUUAAAAUGUUAAAGUAACCUAAAAUGAAUUCAGACCAAUAAAAUCAAGGGAAAUACAAGUUGAUUGCAUUACUUCUGUAUGUUGCUUGCUAUUAAAAAGGUUAAGAGGCCAGGUUACCCACCAGUCCUUGCACUGUUCUGACACUUUCCCCAGGAGGAAAACAAGUACAAAGGUUACGGUGGAGGCAUAAGUAGAAGAGAUUGUUAAGAAGGGUAUUCAUGUGUCUUUGCUCUUUCUGCUUUAUGCCUCAGUUUGGUUUAAAAACUUCUGUACUGGCAAAUGGUGGUAUUCAGUGUGGGAUAGUGUCAUAACUAAUUUGACAAUUUAUUAAUCAUAAAAUAACAAUAAAUCUCUAGCUUUUACA